CUCAUUUUCUCUUGCCGCCACCAUGUAAGAAGCGCCUUUCGCCUCCCUCCAUGAUUCUGAGGCCUCCCCAGCCACAUGGUACUUGUAUGCCUAGACAGCGGGCACAGGGCUUGCUGGACACAGAAGGCAAGGACUCAGAGAAUAUCCACCAGAUGAAAGAAUGACUGCAUGAGUAACCUGAUCCUGCCUGAAGAUGGUGCCACUGGUGGCUGUGGUAUCAGGGCCCCGUGCCCAGCUCUUUGCCUGCCUGCUCAGGCUGGGCACUCAGCAGGUCGGCCCCCUUCAGCUGCACACCGGGGCCAGCCAUGCGGCCAGGAACCAUUAUGAGGUGCUGGUGCUGGGUGGGGGCAGUGGCGGAAUCACCAUGGCUGCCCGCAUGAAGAGGAAAGUGGGUGCAGAGAAUGUGGCCAUUGUUGAGCCCAGUGAGAGACAUUUCUACCAGCCAAUCUGGACACUGGUGGGUGCUGGUGCCAAACAAUUGUCCUCAUCUGGUCGUCCCACGGCAAGUGUGAUUCCAUCUGGUGUAGAAUGGAUCAAAGCUAGAGUGACUGAGUUGAACCCAGACAAGAACUGCAUUCACACAGAUGACGACGAGAAGAUCUCCUACCGAUAUCUUAUUAUUGCUCUCGGAAUCCAGCUGGACUAUGAGAAGAUUAAAGGCCUACCUGAAGGUUUCGCUCAUCCCAAAAUAGGGUCGAAUUAUUCAGUUAAGACUGUAGAGAAGACAUGGAAAGCUCUGCAGGACUUCAAAGAGGGCAAUGCCAUCUUCACCUUCCCAAAUACUCCAGUGAAGUGUGCUGGAGCCCCUCAGAAGAUCAUGUACUUAUCAGAAGCCUACUUCAGGAAGACAGGGAAGCGAUCCAAGGCCAAUAUCAUUUUCAACACUUCUCUUGGAGCCAUUUUCGGGGUUAAGAAGUAUGCAGAUGCCCUGCAGGAGAUCAUCCAGGAGCGGAACCUCACUGUUAACUACAAGAAAAACCUCAUUGAAGUCCGAGCCGAUAAACAAGAGGCUGUAUUUGAGAACCUGGACAAACCAGGAGAGACCCAAGUGAUUUCAUAUGAAAUGCUUCAUGUCACACCUCCAAUGAGCCCACCAGAUGUCCUCAAGACCAGUCCUGUGGCUGAUGCUGCUGGUUGGGUGGAUGUGGAUAAAGAAACUCUGCAACACAGGAGGUACCCAAAUGUGUUUGGGAUUGGGGACUGCACCAACCUUCCUACGUCAAAGACCGCUGCUGCAGUAGCUGCCCAGUCAGGAAUACUUGAUAGGACAAUUUCUGUAAUUAUGAAGAAUCAAACACCAACAAAGAAGUAUGAUGGCUACACAUCAUGUCCACUGGUGACCGGCUACAACCGUGUGAUUCUUGCUGAGUUUGACUACAAAGCAGAGCCGCUAGAAACCUUCCCCUUUGAUCAAAGCAAAGAGCGCCUUUCCAUGUAUCUCAUGAAAGCUGACCUGAUGCCUUUCCUGUAUUGGAAUAUGAUGCUAAGGGGUUACUGGGGAGGACCAGCGUUUCUGCGCAAGUUGUUUCAUCUAGGUAUGAGUUAAGGAUGGCUCAGCACUUGCUCAUCUUGGAUGGCUUCUGGGCCAAAACUGCAGUCACUGAAUGACCAAGAGCAGCACGAAGGACUUGGAACCUAUCCUUGUAAAGAGUUCCUUGAUGGGUAAUGGUGACCAAAUGCCUCCCUUUUCAGUACCUUUGAACAGCAACCAUGUGGGCUACUCAUGAUGGGCUUGAUUCUUUGGGAAUAAUAAAAUGAAAUAAUACUUUUAUUUUCUGAAUAAAAGUUUGUCACUGA